GGAGCCGCCGGGAGGUAGGCGCGGGACGGGCGGCUGCGGUGGCGGCGGGUGGACCGAUUGUCGCUCGGCGGCGGGAGUCGGUGGAGUCUCGCUCUUUCGCAAGGCUGGAGUGCAAUGGCAUGAUCUCGGCUCACUGCAGCCUCCGCCUCCUGGGUUCAAGUGAUUCUUCUGCCUCAGCCUCCCGAGUAGCUGGGACUACAGAAAUGCUGGUAAUUUCAGUCACUUGCUGAUGACUUCUGAUGUCCCAGCAAAUGUUGGCAUUGUUGACUGCUGAGAAGAUACUUCUGAGGACCCACGUCUAAGGUGGACUUGGUUCGCACUCUUCUGGUUAGUCCCUGAACAGGAGUGAUGCCUCCAGGCAGGUGGCAUGCUGCCUAUCCAGCUCAGGCCCAGUCUUCGAGGGAGCGAGGGCGGCUUCAGACAGUAAAGAAGGAAGAAGAGGAUGAAAGCUAUACUCCAGUGCAGGCUGCCAGGCCACAGACUCUCAACCGCCCUGGCCAGGAGCUGUUCCGCCAGCUCUUCAGACAGCUUCGCUACCAUGAGUCUUCAGGGCCCCUAGAAACUCUGAGCCGGCUCCGGGAACUCUGUCGCUGGUGGCUGAGGCCUGACGUUCUCUCCAAGGCACAGAUCCUAGAGCUGCUGGUGCUGGAACAGUUCCUGAGCAUCCUGCCUGGGGAGCUCCGGGUUUGGGUGCAGCUUCAUAACCCUGAGAGUGGCGAGGAGGCUGUGGCCUUGCUGGAGGAGCUGCAGAGGGACCUUGAUGGGACAUCCUGGAGGGACCCGGGCCCUGCCCAGAGCCCAGAUGUGCAUUGGAUGGGUACAGGAGCCCUGCGAUCUGCACAGAUAUGGUCCCUUGCUUCACCUCUCAGGAGCAGCUCUGCUCUGGGGGACCACCUGGAGCCUCCCUAUGAAAUAGAAGCACGUGACUUCCUGGCUGGGCAAUCCGAUACUCCUGCUGCCCAGAUGCCUGCCCUUUUCCCGAGAGAGGGGUGCCCGGGAGACCAGGUAACACCAACCAGGUCCCUGACAGCCCAGCUCCAGGAGACCAUGACUUUCAAGGAUGUGGAGGUGACCUUCUCCCAGGACGAGUGGGGGUGGCUGGACUCUGCUCAGAGGAACCUGUACAGGGAUGUGAUGCUGGAGAAUUAUAGGAACAUGGCUUCCCUGGUGGGACCAUUCACCAAACCUGCUCUGAUCUCCUGGUUGGAAGCAAGGGAGCCAUGGGGCCUGAACAUGCAGGCAGCUCAGCCUAAGGGGAAUCCAGUUGCUGCUCCUACAGGAGAUGACCUCCAGAGUAAAACAAACAAAUUCAUCUUAAAUCAGGAACCUUUGGAAGAAGCAGAAACCUUAGCUGUGUCAUCAGGAUGUCCUGCGACAAGUGUUUCUGAGGGAAUUGGGCUCAGAGAAUCUUUUCAACAGAAGAGCAGGCAGAAGGAUCAAUGUGAAAAUCCCAUACAAGUAAGAGUUAAGAAAGAAGAGACCAAUUUCAGUCACAGGACAGGAAAAGACUCUGAAGUAUCAGGAAGUAAUAGUCUUGACUUAAAACAUGUUACAUAUUUGAGAGUUUCUGGAAGAAAGGAAUCCCUUAAACAUGGCUGUGGCAAACACUUCAGAAUGAGUUCACACCACUAUGACUACAAGAAAUAUGGGAAGGGGCUCAGACACAUGAUUGGGGGCUUCAGCCUACAUCAGAGAAUUCAUAGUGGACUGAAAGGGAACAAAAAGGACGUGUGUGGAAAAGACUUCAGCCUUAGCUCUCAUCACCAACGUGGGCAGAGUCUUCACACAGUGGGAGUGUCAUUUAAGUGCAGUGACUGUGGAAGGACUUUCAGUCAUAGCUCCCAUCUUGCGUAUCAUCAGAGACUUCACACUCAAGAGAAAGCAUUUAAAUGUAGGGUGUGUGGGAAAGCCUUCCGGUGGAGUUCCAACUGUGCGCGGCAUGAGAAAAUUCACACUGGAGUGAAGCCUUAUAAAUGCGAUUUAUGUGAGAAAGCUUUCCGACGCCUGUCAGCCUACCGUCUGCACCGAGAAACCCAUGCUAAGAAGAAAUUUCUUGAAUUGAAUCAGUAUAGGGCAGCUCUCACCUACAGCUCAGGGUUUGAUCAUCAUUUGGGAGACCAAAGUGGGGAGAAACUCUUUGACUGCAGCCAGUGCAGGAAAUCCUUCCACUGUAAGUCAUAUGUUCUUGAACAUCAAAGGAUUCACACCCAGGAGAAGCCCUAUAAAUGUACCAAAUGUAGGAAAACCUUUAGAUGGAGAUCAAACUUUACUCGUCAUAUGAGGUUGCAUGAGGAGGAAAAAUUCUACAAACAAGAUGAAUGUCGUGAAGGCUUCAGGCAAUCUCCUGACUGCAGUCAGCCCCAGGGUGCUCCCGCUGUGGAGAAAACAUUUCUGUGUCAGCAGUGUGGGAAAACUUUUACUAGAAAGAAAACUCUCGUUGACCACCAGAGAAUUCACACAGGUGAGAAACCUUACCAGUGUAGCGAUUGUGGGAAGGACUUUGCCUAUAGGUCAGCCUUUAUUGUUCAUAAGAAGAAGCAUGCCAUGAAAAGAAAACCUGAGGGCGGGCCAUCUUUUAGUCAGGACACAGUGUUCCAGGUUCCUCAGAGCAGUCACUCCAAAGAGGAGCCCUACAAAUGCAGCCAGUGUGGCAAGGCCUUCCGCAAUCACUCAUUCCUCCUCAUCCAUCAGAGAGUUCACACUGGAGAGAAGCCAUAUAAGUGCAGGGAGUGUGGGAAAGCCUUCAGAUGGAGUUCCAAUCUCUACCGACAUCAGAGGAUUCACUCUCUUCAAAAACAGUAUGAUUGCCAUGAAAGUGAAAAGACUCCAAAUGUGGAGCCAAAAAUCCUCACUGGUGAGAAACGUUUUUGGUGUCAAGAAUGUGGGAAAACCUUUACACGUAAAAGAACCCUUUUAGAUCAUAAGGGAAUACACAGUGGAGAGAAGCGCUAUAAAUGUAAUCUAUGUGGGAAAUCUUAUGAUAGAAACUAUCGCCUUGUUAACCAUCAGAGGAUCCACUCUACAGAGAGACCUUUCAAAUGUCAGUGGUGUGGGAAAGAGUUCAUUGGGAGACAUACCCUUUCCAGUCACCAGAGGAAACACACCAGAGCAGCACAGGCUGAACGUAGCCCGCCUGCACGGUCUUCCUCUCAGGACACAAAGUUGAGAUUACAGAAGCUAAAACCAAGUGAAGAGAUGCCCCUCGAAGACUGCAAAGAAGCUUGCAGCCAGAGCUCCAGGCUCACUGGACUCCAGGACAUAAGCAUUGGGAAAAAGUGCCACAAAUGCAGCAUAUGUGGGAAAACUUUUAACAAGAGUUCACAACUCAUUAGCCACAAGAGAUUUCAUACUCGAGAGAGGCCCUUCAAAUGCAGCAAGUGUGGAAAGACCUUCAGGUGGUCUUCGAACCUGGCUCGGCAUAUGAAAAACCAUAUUAGAGAUUAGCCUGGGACCUGACAGUGACAGUGGGGGUGGGUUCUCAGUCCCCUGCUAGAGAACCCUUAAUUAUAGGCAUUGUGGAGUAACUUUGAUAAAGGGCCCAGCCCUUUCUGUUUUGGAAGCUAGUGACAGAAUCCCAAGGAUUUGAAAGCUCGGGGAGUCCCCAGCCUGCCUGCUAGGAUGUGACGCUGGGGAAGUGCAGCACCAUGUCCUUUGGAGCCCUUCUGGAGACUCCGGCCCCUAGGAGUGGCCUCUGCACCAUAGCCUGCGGCUCCCCUAUUCAGGUCUCCUUCCACAACUCUGAAGAGAGAGACCACUGCCCUUUGUGGUUGGACAGAAUAUCUGUGGCAUCAUGGGCUAUGGCUGCUGGAAAGGGGCCAGUGGGAUCCUAGAUUUGUCUUCAAGUUUGGCCUGUGGCCAUGCCUAUUCUGUUGACUUUAAAAGCAGCAGCAUCAAGAACUCCUAGCCUUCCCAAAUGCCCCCUGGGGAGUUCUGGCUGGGGCUUCAGCCUUCCUGGCUGGCUUUUGGAUAUCUGCUAGGGGGUUAGAGUGGUCUCAGCGGCAGGUGGAGGAGAGCAGGAUGCUGGGCUCAAGCGCUUGGCGUGUGGAUCUCUACCAGUACCCUGUUGCCAUCCCCAUCCCACAGGCCUGCAUAGGCAGCAGCGGUCCAUCUGUUUAACAGAAAUGUGCUGAGCACUCCCAUACACCAGGCGCUGGUGUGUUUGCCAGAGACCCAGCAGGGACCAGAACAGAUGAAAAUCCUGCCAUCUUGGAUCUUUACAGAUGACAAACAAAUGGGAUACGCAGUAUUCUGGAUGGUGAUGUGUGUAGUGGACAAAGUGAAUCAGAGAAGAGCAGAGGGAGUGCUGGAUUGGGAGAUCAGUCGUGAUUUUAGAUAGUCUGGUCAGGGAGGGCCUCAACUGAGAAGGUGAAAUGUGAGCAAAGACGUGAAGGAAGCCAGGGAGGUAGCAGGUAGCUCUCUAGGGAGAGUUGCAGGCAGAGGAGAUUGGGUCUUGACUGGUGUCCUCAGGAAGGAAGCCCCUGGGAUGGAGUGCAGGGAGCCAGCUGGAAGGGAAGGAGAGGGGCCAGGGAGGCCACAGGCCCGGCCAUAUGAGCAUCAUGGGUCAUUACGGGGGCUUGAGCUGGCUCAGAGGGAGGCAGGGAGCUUUUGGACAAUUUUGAGUUGAGGAGUGAUGUGGUUUGAAUCUGAAUUAUAUUUUAUAAGGGUUAACCACAGAUCCAAGGACUCAGUAAAAGGGUGAAAGGCUUCUCAUGCAGUUAGCCUUGCUGCCAGUUCCCAUAAAUCAGACUCCUCCCCACUCCGUUUCUGAAUUUUCUAUAGGAUCCUCGGCCUCAGCAGAUAUAAACGCUUACCAUUGUUGUGUUCAUGUCUCUAGCCCCUGCACACUGCAGGCCCCUCUCAGCUUCACAUACCCCUCUCCAUGUAUGAGAUCUGGUGCUAGCAAUCAGAUUCAACCCGAAGGAACAAGUGCAUGUGCCUGCUGCUCUCAGGAGAAAAGGCAGCCUGUUCUGGGAGGAGCUCCCUCACUGGCCCACCCACUUGUGUUGAAGCAAAAAGCAAGAAUCAAUUACUUAAAGGCAAAGGAGUGAUAUUGCUAAAGCAUGUGAGUAAUCAUUGCUUCUGAUUAUUGAAGAGGUCAGAUUAUGAAUGAAAGGAUAAAAUGUUUUAAUAGUAGAGCAGUGUCCUGACUAUAGGGGCCCGUUCAUGGAGCUGGUCAUUUCUUGAAAUGAGAAGAAACCAACCUGGAAGAUGUCUUUUUCAGUAGAGUAUGGAAUAAUCUUACCUGCUCUGGAUUGCCAUGAGCAGGUGAAAAUGAAGGCUCUGAUAUUGUGUGGUGGUGUCACAGGAUGGUGGGGGCGGGGCAGAAGUCUCCUGUUGGUGUUCUGAUGCCUGUUCAGCUUUGUCCUCAGGAAGGUUUGGUCAUCUUGGUUCUGCCAUCCUCUUGCCUUCCUACGGCAGCAGCUGUUCAUGGCACUGAAGAUGUCCCUUCACUGUCCCAAAACUGGCACUAGAAGUGGCUGGGCAGGGGGGCCAGAGUCAUAGGAAGGGUCUUGGAGUCAUCAGAUCUGGGUUCCAGGCAUGGUGUGCCUUUUCUUGGCAGGAUUGAUCUUGAGCAAGUCAAUGAACCUCUGCAUCAAUUUCCUUAUGUGUGAAGUUAGAGUGCUUGGCUGUGCUACCUGAUUCCUGAGAUUGGUGAAAGAGGGCUUGGUUUACCAAGGCUCUCCAUCAGGUGGUUGACCUCUAGGACCAGGGCCCUCUCAGAGGUGCAGCUUCCAUGUCAGUUGGUGUUGUAACCAUGGAAAAGUCCCUUUCCAAUCAAACUUUUAGCACCCCUUUCCCCCCAUCUCUGCUCCCUUUGCCACAGGAUACCUUGUAAAGUUCCUGCCCCAGUAUAGGGAUAUUUUUACUGUCUUUUUUAUUUUUUGAGACAGGGUUGCCCAGGGUGGAGUGCAGUGGCAGGAUCACAGCUUACUGCAGCCUUGACCUCCCAGGCUCAGGUCCCAUCUGAGCCUCCCGAGUAGCUGGGGCUACAGGUGUGUGCCACCCUGCCAGCUAAUUUUUUAUAUUUUUUUGUAGAGACAAAACUUUUAUUUUUUUUUCCCAUGUUGCUCAUGCUGGUCUCAAACUCCUGGGCUCAAGCAAUCCACCCACCUCUGCCUCCCAAAGUGCUGGGAUUACAGGCGUGAGCCACUGUGCCUGACCUGUCAUUUUUAUAGAAUGAAAUGUGCUUAUUUCUAAACAUUCUAAUCAAAUUUUAAAAUGUGCAAAGAAUGAAGUGAAAAACUGAAUUUUUUUUUUUUUUUGAUACGGAGUCUCACUCUGUUACCCAGGCUAGAGUGCAGUGGCGCGAUCUCCGCUCACUGCAAGCUCUGCCUCCUGGGCUCACACCAUUCUCCUGCCUCAGCCUCCUCAGUAGCUGGGACUACAAGUGCCUGCCACCACGCCUGGGUUAUUUUUUAUAUUUUUAGUAGAGACGGGGUUUCACUGUGUUAGCCAGGAUGGUCUCGAUCUCCAGGAUGGUCUCGAUCUCCAGGAUGGUCUCGAUCUCCUGACGUCGUGAUCCACCCGCCUCGGCCUCCCAAAAUGCUGGGAUUACAGGUGUGAGCCACUGUGCCCGGCCAAAAGAACAGAAAUUAUUUUAUCCUGAAGUAAGCUGUUUAUAUUUGGGAUUAUACUGAACCUAUUUGUCCAAUAACCUGAGUUUUCAAAUAAUUUUAGUUCUAUAAGUACUAUAAUUAUAUAAAUAUUAAUGAAUUCAGAUUAGCUGAAAGGAAAAAAAGUAGAAGCCUGACUACUUGGUGCUAACUACUAAAGAUUUUGGCAGAAUCAAUGUUGGAUUUGGCUUUCCUGUCCCUUCCCCAUGCCAGCCCCCCAGAGUGUUCUGCCUUGUGCUGCCUCCCUUCACCUGGAGUGCCACACCCCUCUCUCUGCCAGUUCAGCUCUUCAUUCUUCAAGGCCUGACCUUGUCUGACCCUUGUGCCUCUAAACCCGUGGCCCCACCUCUCUUGGUUCCUAUGUCAGGUGAUGUUUGUGUUUUUGGUUAUGCCCAUCUCCAUAGCCAGACCAAGCACUCUGGAAGCCAGGGUUGGGUGCUUAUUUAUCUGUUUGCCAUGCAGAAAAUAUCUUGCACAAAAUUACCUCUGUUAAGGAAUCUGAAGCUGAAUUUAGUUUGGCUGAGUCAGGGUUGGGUUUUUUUUAAGGGGCUGUGGGGUGAAAUGUUGACUGGAAGCCACCCACAAACACACACCUGCUGGUUAGGAACCCGGCUGUGGGUGGUUCUGAGCUGUUUGGCUUCAGUUGACAGUUUCUGAUUGCCCUGAGCACCAGGUCUCAUCUUGCAUCUCAUCCUGGCCUGGAGAACAUUCAGUUUCCUUCCAACCCUUCCCACCUUUCCCCCACUCCCUUGGAGGAACUGAAGUUGGGGUUGAGGAGAGCCAGAUGGCUGGAGUGGGUAUUUGAAGGUCUUUCUGUCACCUGUUCAGUGUGGUCUGCCCCACCCCUGCUGACCAAGACUGACUGAAAUGUAAAAUAAUACAGACCAUCUCACACUCAGAAAGCUGGCACAUUUUUGAAAGCCCAAGUGUGGGUAAGUGCGUGGAACAACGAUAAUUCACACUGCUUUAUGAGUAGAAAUUGUGAGAAAUAUUGUGCCAGGCAAUUUGCAAAAUCUUGGAAGGUUGUGUGCACUUAACCACCCAGCAACUACUCCUGGAUGCAUCCUAGAGAAGUGCCAUGUGAACAGAGAAUGAUUUUAAGACUUCACUGAAGUAUUGUUUAGGUAGCAAGAUUGGGAAAAGCCUGCAUUUCAUCAGCAGAAGAAUGGAUAAAUAAAUGGGUUGUUUUUGGUCCUUGGAAAGUGAAUAUGAAAGAGUUACGUCUCAACACAGAUAGAUGAAAAAUUAUGCUGAGAAAGUUGGUGAAGCUACAUACAAGGUACCCUUAGUGUAAAGUUAAGCAUACUGUGUACCUGUGGGCACGUUACUUCAACUUGUUUUUCACUUUUUCUGUAAAAUGGGAUAGUAGUGGCAAUCUCACAGGGUGAUUGUGGGUGGGGGGGUGGUCAAUGAAGUAAUGCAUGUAAAAUGCUUAGAAUAGUGUCUAGCAUGUAAGCCUUGUGGACAUAUAGAAAGUGUUAUUGUUUUGCACAGUAAUCUAUUUUCUGUGGAUUCAAAUAAUAUGAAAUGAGUAUAAAAUCAUGUAUUGGAACGAUGUGUGCAAGUCACCAUUCUGCCUUCCUAAGGCAGGAGACCUGAUGGAUUUGGGGAGGGUACAUGGGGCCUUCAGUUGUGUUUUCUUUGUUUUUUUCUAAAAAUUGAUGCAGAGGCAUCACAAUGUUAAGAUUUUUACAGGGUAGUGUGGUGGGUACUUUUUAACUGUUUGCUUAAAGUGUUUCAAAGUAAAAAUAUUUCUUAAGCAUAGUCUCUGACAUCUUAUGACUUUAUAGAAAUCCCUGCCAGGUACAUGAUGUUACUUAGAGUGAGCCACCUAAUCUUUCAAGGCUUCCAUUUCCUCACCUGCAAAAAUUGGGAGUGUCAGAGGCGUUUGAACCAGAGUGACUCCAUCUUGAAUAGGGAACUGGGUAAAAUAAGGCUGAGACCUACUGGGCUGCAUUCCCAGGAGGUUAGGCAUUCCAAGUCAUGGGAUGAGAUAGGAGGUCAGCACAAGAUACAGUCAUAAAGACCUUGCCAAUAAAACAGCAUGUGGUAAAGAAGCCGGUCAAAACCAAGAUGGCAAUGAAAGUGACCUCUGGUUGUCCUCACUGCUGUAAUUAUACUGUAAUUAUAAUGCAUUAGCAUGCUAACAGACACUCCCACCAGUGCCAUGACAGUUUACAAACGCCAUGGCAGGCCUGGCACGAUGGCUCAUGCCUGUAAUCCCAGCACUUUGGGAGGCCAAGGCGGGCGGAUUAUGAGGUCAGGAGAUUGAGACCAGCCUGGCCAACAUGGUGAAACCCUGUCUCUACUAAAAAAUACAAAAAUUAGCUGGGCAUGGUGGCACGUGCCUGUAAUCCCAGCUACUUGAGAGGCUGAGGCAGGAGAAUCUCUAGAUCCCGGGAGUUGGAGGUUGCAGUGAGCCAAGAUGGUGCCACUGCACUCCAGCCUGGGUGACAGAGCAAGACUCUGUCUCAAAAAAAAAAAAAAAAAAUGCCAUGGCAACAUCAGGAAGUAACACUAUAUGGUCUAAAAAGGAGAGGAACCCUCAGUUCUGGUAAUUGCUCACACCUUUCCCGGGAAACUUAUGAAUAAUCUACCCCUUGUUUAGCAUAUAAUCAAUAAAUAACCAUAAAAAUAGGCAACCAGCAGCCCUUGGGGCUACUCUUCCUAUGGAGUAGCCAUUCUGUAUUUCUUUACUUUCUUAAUAUUAACUACUUUCACUUUGUGGACUCGCCCGAAUUCUUUUCUUGAGCAAGGUCCAAGAACUCUCUCUUGGGGACUGGAUCACGACCGCUUUCUGGUAACAGGAGCAAUACAAAUGGCUAUUAGUAAACGAACGCUUAAGUAACUCUAGUACAUCUAUGAUGAAAUACCAGGCCACAGUUUUUUUAAAAAUGAGGAUGUUCUCUAUAUACUGACGCACAGUCACCAAGACAUGCACUUUAUAGGAAAUUAUAAGCUCCUCCUUGCCUAAAUCUCCUUAAUUUUGCUUAAUAAAUAACAAGUGAAGCCAGAAGCUGUAAACUCAUAAUUUUAAUGAAGAAAUGGGAUCCAGAAGAUGGAGAUGUUUUUCAUUCUACUUUAUUAGAUGAGGAAAAGGAGAGUAAAUACUUGUAUGCCAGCUACCACACCUUUUAAAGUUAAUGUUAACCCUGCUAAGAACAGCAAGGAGAUUUUAUAUCAGCCAGGUUUUAGUUGCCAGAAACCACACCAGUUAUUUUAGCAAAGACCUUAUAAAGAAGUGUACUAUAUUUAAGUAGCUAAAAAGGCAAGAAGAAAAUGCCAAGGUGUCUUGGAGGUAGCAACUGCUAAGCAGCUGCCACCCCAGGACUGGGGGAGCUAGAAUAGAGUCUCCCCAUGUUUGACGUUUGUCUGCUAAUAGCAUUCAAGCUCUCCCCCUCAGUUUGCCUGGAUCUGGACAAGCUGAUAAGAAAGCCCAGCCACUUCCUCUUUGCGUCAGAGGGGAAGUUCAAACUGUGCAAACCCUGACUGUCAAAUGCACUGAGCUCUCAUAACCACAACAAAAACCAGAGCCACUUGUUCGUCCUUUCACUGAAGCCCAACAGACUGGCGUGGGUGCCCGCUUUGCUUUCCCUAGAAGGCCUCAUGUGAGUAGUAAACUUUUUCAUAACCUCUUGGUGUCUGCAGUGUCAUCAGUUUCAACAUCCGAACCAGUUUUGAGUGAUGGUAGUUUAUUGAUCCCACCUCAUGUGGAGCAAAGUGCAAAGCAGGAACAAAGAGACGUGGCUAGAAUUGUUGAAAGGUGGGAGAUUGGAAGAGGGACCUUGUGGAGCUGAACUCAGACCUAUGGUGGAGGAGUGGACUGCUGGGCUGACAUAGUGUCUGUGCUCAGGGAGGGGCCCUGUGGCCUUUGGAUCUGUGCUUCUGUGGAGAGGUCCCAGCUACUAAUGCUGGGGCAGGGAGCAGAAGGGAGGGUCACAAUGAGACUUUGAGUGUUAGUUAACCACCUUUUGCCUGAAGAACAUGUAAUGGCCUUCCCUGAGGUAUAUGUCUUCCAAAAGUCCGCUGACGUUGCUCAUGACCUAUGGUCACCACUGCUUUUUGCGUUUUGCUUUUUUUUUUUUUUUUUUUUUGAGACAAGGUCUCACCCUGUCACCCAGGCUGGAGUGCAGUGGCACGAUCUCAGCUCACUGCAACCUCCACUUUCCCAGGCUCAAGCGAUUCUCCAGCCUCAGCCUCCUGACUAGCUGGGACUACAAGCGUGCACCACCACACCCAGCUAAUUUUUGUAUUUUUGUAGAGACAAGGUUUGGCCAUGUUGCCCAAGCUGGUCUUGAACUCCUGACCUCAAGUGACCCACCUGCCUCAGCUUGCCAAAGUGCUGGGAUUACAGGUGUGAGCCACCAUGCCUGGAGUCCUUGUUUUUUUUUUUUUUAUACUUUUAGGGUACAUGUGCACAAUGUGCAGGUUAGUUACAUAUGUAUACAUGUGCCAUGCUGGUGCGCUGCACCCACUAACUCAUCAUCUAGCAUUAGGUAUAUCUCCCAAUGCUAUCCCUCCCCCCCUCCCCCCACCCCACAACAGUCCCCAGAGUGUGAUGUUCCCCUUCCUGUGUCCAUGUUUUCUCAUUGUUCAAUUCCCACCUAUGAGUGAGAAUAUGCGGUGUUUGGUUUUUUGUUCUUGCGAUAGUUUACUGAGAAUGAUUAUUUCCACCUUCAUCCAUGUCCCUACAAAGGACAUGAACUCAUCAUUUUUUAUGGCUGCAUAGUAUUCCAUGGUGUAUGUGUGCCACAUUUUCUUAAUCCAGUCUAUCAUUGCCUGGAGUCCUUUUAAAAAAAUUAUUUUUUUGGCCAGGCACGGUGGCUCACACCUGUAAUCCCAGCACUUUGGGAGGCUGAGGCGGGCAGAUCACGAGGUCAAGAGAUCGAGACCAUGCUGGCUAACGCGGUGAAACCCCGUCUCUAGUAAAAAUACAAAAAAUUAACCGGGCGUGGCAGCGGGCGCCUGUAGUCCCAGCUACUCGGGAGGCUGAGGCGGGCAGAUCACGAGAUCAGGAGAUUGAGACCAGCCAGCCUGGCCAAUAUGGUGAAACCCCAUCUCUAUUAAAAAUACAAAAAUUAGCCGGGUGUGGUGGUGUGUGCCUGUAAUCCUAGCUACUGGGGAGGCUGAGGCAGGAGAAUCACUUGAACCCAGGAGGUGGAAGUUGCAGUGAGCCGAGAUCGCACAACUGCACUCCAGCCUGGGCGACAGAGUGAAACUUUGUCUCAAUUAAAAAAAAAAAAAAGUGAAGUGCAAAAUGUGACUGAGGAGAUACAGUACUCUCCAAAUUGCAUAAUUUUGCCAAUUUUUAUAGAAACCUGGGGAAUCUGUAGAGAUAGCGUCAGAAGCAUUGGAACGAGAGCAACUCCAUGUUGAAUAGGGGCUGGGUAAAAGUGUCAGAGGUAUUUGAACCAGAGCGACUCCAUUUUGAGUGAGGGCUGGGAAAAUGAGGCUGAGACUUACUGGCCUGCAUUCUCAGAAAGUUAGGCAUUCCUACCCUCUAGGAUUGAAUUGGGACCCCUUUCCUGUAACAUAUUUCUGGUGACCACAGAAGGGACUAUAGUGCAGAAACGUUGACCCAACGGCUACCUUUGCGUAAGUGUUGGGGUCCUGUAACAUAUUUCUGGCAAACCACAGAAAGGAUGAUACUGAAGAAAUCCCCCCAACCCCAAAGAAAUAGACUGCAGCACUGAUUGGACGACUUUGGGUAAGUGAUGGGGUACCCGAGUAACAAAUGGGAUUGGGUUAGAGGCCCAACUUAGGGGAGUUGGAGUUUCUCCUAAGACAGAGUGAGUUAGAGGCCCCUCUUAAUAAAAGGCAAGGACACUUGACUGACCUCAGGUUAGAGGUUACUCCAUCCUACUCUAUGGAGUAGCUGUCCUUUCACCACUUUACUUUCUUAAUAAACUUGUUUUUGCUUUGCACUGCGGACUUGCCCUGAAUCCUUUCUUGCACGAGAUCCAAGAACUCUCUUAAGAGUCUGGAUCGGGACCCCUUUCCUGUAACAAAAUGAGGCUGAGACCUACUGGGCUGCAUUCCCAGACGGUUAAGGCAUUCUAAGUCACGGGAUGAGAUAGGAGAUUGGCACAAGAUCCAGGCCACAAAGACCUUGCUGAUAAAGCAGGUUGCAGUAAAGAAGCCAGCUAAAACCCACCAAAACCAAGACGGUGAUGAGAAUGACCUCUGGUCAUCCUCACUGCUACCCUCCCACCAGUGCCAUGACAGUUUACAGUUGCCAUGGCAACAUCAGGAAGUUACCCUAUAUGGCCUGGAGAGGGGAGGCAUGAAUAAUCCACCCCUUGUUUAGCAUAUCAUCAAGAAACCAUAAAAUAGACAACCAGCAGCCCUCGGGGCUGCUCUGUCUAUGGAGUAGCCAUUCUUUUAUUCCUUUACUUAAUAAACUUGCUUUCUCUUUACGGACUCGCCCUGAAUUCUUUCUUGUGCGAGAUCCAAGAACCCUCUCUUGGGGUCUGGAUUGGGAACCUUUUGCGGUAACAAGGGUGCAGGAUCAUCGUGGAAGGAAUAUAAAGUCAGAUCAAGCUGAAUUAUUCGAUAUGGGAUAAUUAAGCAGAGAUUUGUGGUUCAUUGUUUUAACUUGAGAAGCUGAGAAUGGCUGUCUUCAUUUGCUUUGAGUUGUUGAGAUAUGGACUCACUGUAAUCCCAGCUUGGGAGGCUGAGGUGGGAGGAUUGCUUGAGGCCAGGAGUUUGAGACUGGCUUGGGCAAUAUAGUGAGAACUCAUCUCCAAAAGAAAAAAAAAACACGAAUGCAAACAUAACCUGCACUGAAUGAGUUGAAAUGCGAGAACUUCGUUGGUAUACUGUAGAGGAAGAUAUGUAAAUGCUUAAGGAGAUAAAAAUGCUUGAGUAUUUAUCAUGUAAAUACCUGCUCACCCACCCAGGGAGGGUCCAGAGGACACUUCAUUAUGAGAAAUAAAUUCAUGUAGAGAGUGCCAGAUAUUCUAUACAGGCCACAUUACAGUGGGAAAUGCUCCCUGAAGUGCAGUGGGGCUGAUGGAAUCCUGAGGAGGCAGGGACCAUAUGGUAACACUUAGUCACCAAAAACACAAUUGGUGUGGUGACUGCCAUGGACAGUGCAGCCAAAGCAGGAUCCUGAAUGGUCUGACCCACAGAGAUCUGUGAUGUCUGCCUGCUGAUCAUAGUGUCCUGAGAACUGAAAUGGAUGGGCUGCCUACUAAAGUUUUACUUGAUCCGAGUAAGUAGGAAAGCUCCAGAUCUGGUGAAUAAAGUCUGACCUAAAUUACCAACACAGAGUUACAAUCACUCAGUCAAUUCCAAGUCUUGAUCUAGUUCACAAACCCACAGCUUCUUGAAUAAAGGAUAGGCCAGGUCCCUUUGAAGUAGGACCCUGCUGCACUGACAAUAAUUUAUACUUUUUAUCUUCCUAGGCCUCCCCAAAGGCACCCAAGGCCAUUUAUCAGAGUGAUUGUGCAUUGGGAAGGGCAAAUAAUUAGACUUUUCUGGGAUAACCAGCCUCUAGUUCUGAACUAGCAGUAAUUACAGGAGACUCAAAAUGCCACCAUGGUUCCUCAGAGUAAGAGUGUAUGGAGGUCAGGUGAUCAAUGGGCUUUUUGGCUCAGAUUCAUCUCACAGUAGAUCUAGUAGAUUCCUGAACCCAUCCUAUGGUUAUUUCCCUGGUUCUAGAAUGCGUAAUUAGAAUAGACAUAGUCAACAAUGGGCAGAAUCCCACACUAGUUCCCUGAUCCAUACAGUAAAAGUAAUUCUGGUAGAAAAGGCCAAGUAGAAGCCACUAGAGCUGCCUCAUUCACAAAAAUAUUAAAGCAAACUAAUACCACAUUCCUGGAGAGAUUGUUGAGAUUAGUGCCACCAUCAAAGACGGGAACACAUCUCCACUUAGCUCACCUACUCAGCCUGUGCAGAAGACAGAUGGAUCUUGGAGAAUGACAAUUGGAUUAAUUGUAAACUUAAUUAACUAGUGAUUCCAAGUGCAGGUGCUGUUUCCACAUGUGGUUUCAGUGCUGAGCAAACGAUACGUCUGACAACUGGUUUGCAGUUGUUACUGAGCCAGGCCCAGGUUUGUUCUGUUCUCACACAGUAAAUCAAUCACUGUGACAUGGGUUUUGCAAAAGAGAGAAGAAUUAUUCACAAGGCUGUCCAGUGAGGAGAUGGGAGAAUGGCUCUCAAAUUCACCUCCCCAAAGAUGAGGCUUAGAGAGAUUUAUAGGUUAGAGAAGUAGGGUGGUCUGAGGCAUGGGGAAAGGUGAUUGGCAGUGGGGAAAAAUGCAGUCAUAAUUGGGGUUCAUAUGACAUAUGUGCAGAAAAUGGUGGCGUUAACAUGAUCUGAGGGUGGAGUUUUUGGCCCUCUGAUGUCAAAAGGCCACCUCUUGGGCAUGUGUACAGGCCCAGUUGAAGGGUUGGCAGUCUCAACUGGUUUGAACUGGACAGGAUCUGCCCCAAGUUCCUGAAAAAUAAGUGGUUGUUAUGGUGACUUAUAAAUGUUAUCUAUAAGGUAGCACGUAAAAGUUGAGUUACAGUGUUCAAUAGCAUAGCCUUCAGCUAUCGUGGCCUUCAGCUUCAUGGGGGAAAAAAUAACAAAGAGCAAGCAACCAAAAGCAAGCGGGGCAGGCGAAGUGUGGCACACCCGAUCCGAUUAUCCCCUUGGCUGCCCAGUUACCCAUCUGGUGAAUGUUUCUCUAUACCUGUGAGUAAAGACCAUCAGGAACAGUUUGCUUUCAGCUAGAUACACCUUCACCACCCUAUCUCAAGGCUGCCUCAACUCUGCCGCCCAGCUCAUGAUCUAGUUCCCAGGUCCUUUGAGAACCUUUUCACCCUCAGGACGACACACUGGUCCAUUAUAUUGAUGACAUUAUAGUCACUGGACCUGGUGUACAGGGAGUAGCAACUGCUCCAGACAUGUUGGAAGACACAUAAUAUGACUCAGUGUAGGAAAUAAACCCACAACAUGGCUAAGGGCAAAUAAUGUUUCCAAAACUUCUUUCUCUCUUUUUUUUUUCUUUUUUGAGACAGAGUCUCACUCUGUAGCUCGAGCUGGAGUGGAGGCAAUCUUGGCUCACUGCAACCUGCACCUCCUGGGUACAAGUGAAGCUGCUUCCUCAGCCUGUUGGGACUACAGGUGUGCGCCACCACGCCCGGCUAAUUUUUUUUUUUUUUUUUUUGGUAAAGGCAGGGUUUCACCAUGUUAGCCAGCUUGGUCUUGAACUCUUGACCUCAAGUGAUCUGCCCACCUCAGCCUCCCAAAGUGCUGGGAUUACAGAAGUGAGCCACCAAGCCAGGCCCUUUUUCUCUCUCUUUCCAAUAGUUACAUUCUAUAUGUUUAAAAGGGACACGAGACAAUUUUGUAUGUGAUUUUCUGAAUCACAUAAUUCCACAUUUAACAUUUUGGGGAAAUGCCAAACUGUUUUCCAAAGGGGCUGCCUGGGAGUCUCAGCUCUAGUUCUCAGUCCUCAGCAGCCAUUCCUUUCCUCAGUGGGGCGUCAGUGCUGCCUUCCAAAGUCCAGGGCUGCCUUGAGACCUGAUCAGGACCGGCUAUUUUGCCAGGUGCAGUGCAUGAUGUUCAAGACCAUUCAGAAUUUCAAGACCCUGACAGCAGAGCAAGAUAGCAGGCGGAGGCCAUUCUAAGUGUGGGGCCCCGCAGGGCUGCCCAGGCUGCCUGCCUGUGAAGCCAGUCCUGCCUGAUGGAGAUGCUUUUGCCAUGGCGUGAGGGAAAGUGAGCUGAUGGUUCUCCACUUUCCCACUCUCUCUCUGCAGGUCCGGCUCCUCUAAGGGCAGAAGCCAGAACUUGGUCCCUGAACCUUCUCCAGUCUCCCUCCCUGGGCAUUUCUCUCAUAACCCCAUCAGACCCCCCAGUAAUGGCCUGACGUGGGUUCUGGAAAUAGAACAUGGGUUCUUAGAAUGGCUCUCUGAGACUUCAUUGAGUUGUCUGUCCUAUUUCUUUCCUCAACAAAAUGUCCACAUCCUCAAUCUCCUGUCUCAGCAGGAAAGAUGAAAAGAACAGUGAGGCUUAGGCCAGGCACGGUGGCUCACACCUGUAAUCCCAACACUUUGGGAGGCUGAGGUGGGCAGAUCACCUGAGAACGGGAGUUCGAGACCAGUCUGAACUCCCUGUCUCUACUAAAAAUACAAAAGUAGCCAGGCGUGGUAGCGGGCACCUGUAAAUCCCAGCUACUGGGGAGGCUGAGACAGGAGAAUCGUUUGAACCUGGGAGGCGGACGUUGUGGUGAGCCGAGAUAGUGCCACUGCACUCCAGCCUGGACAACAGAGCGGGAAAAAAAAAAAAAAAGAACGAUGACCCUUAGCAUCCCAGGAAGCUUUGGGUGGUGAGAGAUGGAGAGUAUCUCCUUCCUGUGGUACUUCAGUUUCCCGUCUCCUUGUUAGGAUGUUGCAAAGCUGGCCUGCUGAGGUCUUCUGUGAUCUCCUGUGCUUCCUACACUUCCACCUGAAAAUGAACCUACUGCAGGGAUGAAUCCAUGAGCAGAAUUUUAAUGAAAAGGAAGCAGACACAAAGGAAUCCAUGGGUUGUAACUCCACCGACUUAAAAUGAAAAACACAGGCAACAAAGAACAGGCACGAUGCUGCUUCGCCAGCUGGUUCCUUGUUGGGUUCUGCCAUUCAGGGAUGUAAGAGGGAAGCUGGGAUGUUGGAGGACUGGAGUGUGAGGGUAAAUUUUAGGUGUCAACUUGGCUGAGCCACAAGGUCCCCAGGUAUUUGAUCAAACAUUAUGCUGGGUGUUUCUGUGAGGUUGCUUUGGAUGAGAUUAACGUUUAAAUUUGUGGACUUUGAGGAAAGCAGAUUGCCCUCUAUCUGUGGGUGGGCUUCAUCCAAUCACCUGAAGACCUGAGGAGAACAUAAAGUCUGGCUGCCCCAGACUCUCUCUCAGGCAAGAGAGAAUUCUUCCGCAGACUGCCUUCAGAGUUCAUGCACACCAUCUACUAAUCCUGCUCCACAGCAGGUGCCACUGGGCUCUCACUGGAAUAUGUAUUCUCCUGGUUCUCCAGCCUGCUCAUCCACCCUGAAGAUUUGGGACUUGCCAGCCUCCUUAAUUCUAUAAGCCAAUUCCUUAUCAUAAAUUCAUAAAUCCCUCUCUCUCUAUCUCCAUCCACACACACACACACACACACACACACACACACACAGACACACACACACAAAUGAGUGUAGAUGUGUUCCAAUAAAACUUCAUUUAGAGACAUUGAAAUUUAAAUUUCAAGGGCUGGGCAUGGUGGCUCAACGCCUGUAAUCUCAGCACUUUGGGAGGCUGAGGCAGGUGGAUCACUUGAGGUCAGGAGUUCGAGACCAGCCUGGCCAACAUGGUGAAACCCCGUCUCUACUAAAAAUACAAAACAUGUAGCCACGUGCAGUGGCUCAUGCCUGUAAUCCCAGCUGGGAGGCUAAGAUGGGAGAAUAGCUUGAACACAGGAGGCAGAGGUUGCUGUGAGCUGAAAUGGUGCCCAGAAGACAGAGCGACCCUGUCUCAAAAAAAUAAAAAAUAAAAAAUAAAUUUCAUAUAAUCUUCAGAUAUAUUCAUUCAUUUACAUAUUGUCUGUGGUUGUUUUCACCCUUUAGGUCAGAAGUAGCCGACAACCUUUACACAGUAUUUACCACUGUUAUAGACAUCUUUAAAUAUGGUUUACUUUUGCCUGUUUUUGUACUUUAUAGAAAUGAAGUAAUAAAGUAUUGUCUGUCUUGCAUUUUUUGCUCAAAA